AGGGCCGGGCCAGAAGCCCAUCCGACAUCCAGCUGACCCUCACCCUCUGACCCCAGCCCUCAGCGCCAUGAGUCGGGGGCAAAGAGUUCUCAAGGGUCUGCUGGGCUGGGUUUGCACUUGGACCUGGGCCUGGAGAGCCAGACUUGGAGCAAGGGGCUGUGGCCUUCAUGUCCUGUGCCCCAGAGAUCUGCCCCUCCCACCCGAGGCAGCCCAGGACCAGGUGGACGUGGGGACCCAGACGGACGUGGGGACCCAGACGGACAGGGCCCGGUAACCUGGAUUGUUCUGACUUCCUGGACGUCUUUGCCCCCAGGGUUUCGGUUCUGGGCCUCAGUUUCCCCACCUGUCCUCGACCUGACCCACUUCACGGGGCUGCAGGGCGGGUGAUGGGGGGGACCCUACUCUGCCCGGCCCUGCUGGGGCCCGGCCACACCCUAGGGUCUGCAGGAGAGGCGGUGGAGCGGGCUUGCCUUCAGGGAAAAGGGGGCUGCAGGGGCGCAGCUUCGGCCUGUGCGUGUGUCUGGGGUCUGAGGGCGAGGCUCCAGGGGCUUGGUGGCGUCUGAGCGCGUGUGGAGGUCCGGGUCUCUGCGUGUCAUCGUGCACGUGUCUGUGCACGCCCACUCGCGUCCGGGAGUGAGAGUCAGCGCCCUGCAGUCGGCCGCCCCGUGCCCGCCAGCGUCAGGCAGGGGCUCCCGGUCCCACCCCGCGAGCGGCGCGGCUCCGAGCUCCCGAAGGCGGAAGCGGGGGGCGCGGCCCGGGGCUGGGGGCGGGGCCUGCGACCUCACCUUCGCGCCCACUCCGCAGAGCCGCAGGCUGAGGCCGGGAAGGGUCGGGGGCGAGGCCGCGUCGCCGCCUCCCCGAAGCCUUUUCCUGUUGGGGGGAGGGCCCGCCAGUGACGGCCGGGCCUGUCACGUGGGCCUGACAGCUGGGGAGGGGGUGGCCGGCGACAAUGUGGUCCCGAAGCGGCCAGCGCCGGGAGCUGCAGCGCUGAGACCCCCAGCCCGCCCCCUCGGGCUCCCGGCCGGGGCCCCAUCAUGUUCUCCAGGAAGAAACGAGAGCUCAUGAAAACCCCUUCCAUCUCGAAAAAGAACCGCGCGGGAAGCCCCAGCCCGCAGCCCUCGGGGGUGAGUGGAGCCCGGGUGAGACCCGGAGCUGACGCCGGGCCGCAGGGGGACAGGGACCCGCCCUGUGCUCGGGGCUCAUGCUGGGGCGGCGGCUGGGGGCUCGUGCCAGCUACAGCCCCUACCGGGCGGGACGGCAGGGGCCACAGCAGAGAGGCCGGGACCCCGGCAUUCAGCUCACGGAGCUGCCCAGGAAGGAUGGGGCUGACGCGGUGUUCCCCGGACCAAGCCUGGAGCCGCCCGCUGGGUCCUCCGGCGUCAAGGCCACAGGGACCCUCAAGCGGCCCACCAGCCUGAGCCGCCACGCCAGCGCGGCUGGCUUCCCCCUGUCGGGUGCUGCCUCCUGGACACUGGGCCGGAGCCACCGGAGCCCACUGACAGCCGCCAGCCCGGGCGAGCUGCCCACCGAGGGUGCCGGCCCGGACGUCGUCGAGGACAUCUCCCAUCUGCUGGCGGACGUGGCCCGCUUCGCUGAGGGCCUUGAGAAACUUAAGGAGUGUGUGUUGCGUGACGACCUCCUUGAGGCCCGCCGCCCGCGGGCCCACGAGUGCCUGGGUGAGGCUCUGCGUGUCAUGCAUCAGAUCAUCUCCAAGUACCCGCUGCUGAACACCGUGGAGACGCUCACCGCAGCCGGCACCCUCAUUGCCAAGGUCAAAGCCUUCCAUUAUGAGAGCAACAAUGAUCUGGAGAAACAGGAGUUCGAGAAGGCCCUGGAGACGAUUGCUGUGGCCUUCAGUAGCACAGUGUCCGAGUUCCUCAUGGGUGAAGUGGACAGCAGCACCCUCCUAGCAGUGCCUCCUGGGGACUCGAGCCAGUCCAUGGAAAGCCUGUAUGGACCGGGCAGUGAGGGCACGCCUCCCAGCCUGGAAGACUGUGACGCCGGCUGCCUGCCCGCCGAGGAGGUGGACGUGCUGCUACAGCGCUGUGAGGGGGGCGUGGAUGCCGCACUGCUGUAUGCCAAGAACAUGGCCAAGUACAUGAAGGACCUCAUCAGCUACCUGGAGAAGCGGACGACGCUGGAGAUGGAGUUUGCCAAGGGCCUGCAGAAGAUCGCUCACAACUGCAGACAGAGCGUCAUGCAGGAGCCCCACAUGCCGCUCCUGUCCAUCUACUCGCUGGCCCUGGAGCAGGACCUGGAGUUCGGCCACAGCAUGGUGCAGGCGGUGGGCACCUUGCAGACCCAGACCUUCAUGCAGCCCCUGACCCUGCGGCGGCUUGAACACGAGAAGCGCAGGAAGGAGAUCAAGGAGGCCUGGCACCGUGCCCAGAGGAAGCUGCAAGAGGCGGAGUCCAACCUGCGCAAGGCCAAGCAGGGUUACGUGCAGCGCUGCGAGGACCACGACAAGGCUCGCUUCCUCGUGGCCAAGGCGGAGGAGGAGCAGGCUGGCAGCGCGCCGGGAGCAGGCAGCACGGCCACCAAGACCCUGGACAAGCGGCGGCGGCUGGAGGAGGAGGCCAAGAACAAGGCGGAGGAAGCUAUGGCCACCUACCGCACCUGCGUGGCCGACGCGAAGACGCAGAAGCAGGAGCUGGAGGAUACCAAGGUGACGGCGCUGCGGCAGAUCCAGGAGGUCAUCCGGCAGAGCGACCAAACCAUCAAGUCGGCCACGAUCUCCUACUACCAGAUGAUGCAUAUGCAGACGGCGCCGCUGCCCGUGCACUUCCAGAUGCUGUGUGAGAGCAGCAAGCUGUAUGACCCAGGCCAGCAGUACGCCUCCCACGUGCGCCAGCUGCAGCGGGACCAGGAGCCCGAUGUGCACUACGACUUUGAGCCCCACGUCUCCGCCAACGCCUGGUCCCCCGUCAUGCGUGCCCGGAAGAGCAGCUUCAACGUGAGUGAUGUGGCGCGGCCGGAGGCUGCCGGGAGCCCCCCAGAAGAAGGCGGGUGCACUGAGGGCACACCUGCCAAGGACCACAGGGCCGGGCGAGGACACCAGGUUCACAAGUCAUGGCCGCUCUCGAUCUCAGACUCGGACAGUGGGCUGGACCCCGGCCCUGGCGCAGGGGACUUUAAGAAGUUCGAGCGGACGUCAUCCAGUGGUACCAUGUCGUCCACGGAGGAGCUGGUGGACCCAGACGGUGGAGCCGGGGCUUCAGCCUUUGAGCAGGCUGACCUCAACGGCAUGACCCCCGAGCUGCCGGUGGCCGUGCCCAGUGGACCGUUCCGCCACGAGGGGCUGUCCAAGGCGGCCCGUACUCACCGGCUCCGGAAGCUCCGCACGCCCGCCAAGUGCCGCGAGUGCAACAGCUACGUCUACUUCCAGGGUGCUGAGUGUGAAGAGUGCUGCCUGGCCUGCCACAAGAAAUGUCUGGAGACGCUGGCCAUACAGUGCGGGCACAAGAAGCUGCAAGGCCGCCUGCAGCUGUUCGGCCAGGACUUCAGCCACGCGGCCCGCAGCGCCCCCGACGGCGUGCCCUUCAUCGUCAAGAAGUGCGUCUGCGAGAUCGAGCGGCGGGCGCUGCGCACCAAGGGCAUCUACCGGGUCAAUGGGGUAAAGACACGCGUGGAGAAGCUGUGCCAGGCCUUCGAGAACGGCAAGGAGCUGGUCGAGCUGUCGCAGGCCUCGCCCCACGACAUCAGCAACGUCCUCAAGCUCUACCUGCGUCAGCUUCCCGAGCCGCUCAUCUCCUUCCGCCUCUACCACGAGCUCGUAGGGCUGGCCAAGGACAGCCUGAAGGCAGAGGCCGAGGCCAAGGCGGCGUCCCGGGGCCGGCAGGACGGCUCGGAGAGCGAGGCAGUGGCGGUGGCCCUGGCAGGUCGGCUGCGGGAGCUCCUGCGGGACCUGCCGCCUGAGAACCGGGCCUCGCUGCAGUACCUGCUGCGUCACCUACGCAGGAUCGUGGAGGUGGAGCAGGACAACAAGAUGACCCCCGGGAACCUGGGCAUCGUGUUCGGGCCCACGCUGCUUCGGCCACGGCCCACCGAGGCCACCGUGUCCCUCUCCUCCCUGGUGGAUUAUCCCCAUCAGGCCCGCGUCAUCGAGACUCUCAUCGUCCACUACGGCCUGGUCUUCGAGGAGGAGCCGGAGGAGACCCCCGGGGGCCAGGACGAGUCAUCCAACCAGCGAGCUGAGGUAGUCGUCCAGGUGCCGUACCUGGAGGCGGGCGAGGCGGUGGUCUACCCGCUGCAGGAGGCGGCGGCGGACGGGUGCAGAGAAUCCCGAGUUGUGUCCAACGAUUCGGACUCGGACCUAGAGGAGGCCUCCGAGCUGCUGUCCUCAUCGGAGGCCAGUGCCCUGGGCCACCUCAGCUUCCUGGAGCAGCAGCAGAGCGAGGCCAGCCUAGAGGUGGCUUCUGGCAGCCACAGCGGCAGUGAGGAGCAGCUGGAGGCCACAGCCCGGGAGGACGGGGACGGGGACGAGGACGGCCCGGCCCAGCAGCUCUCAGGAUUCAACACCAACCAGUCCAACAACGUGCUGCAGGCCCCACUGCCCCCCAUGAGGCUCCGUGGCGGGCGGAUGACACUGGGCUCCUGCAGGGAAAGGCAGCCGGAAUUCGUGUGAGCUGGGGUGGGGCUGGGACCACAGGUGGCUUCUCUCUUGCCUGCUCCUGUCCCUCCAGCACGUCCCCUGCACCACGGCAUAGCUUAGGUGCGCCGUCCUGGGGUCGCUGCCGAGAGCGCCUGGACUUCGACGUCCCACCAGCGGGCGCCUCCUCCCAGAGGCUUCCAGGAGCACGAGGGCCUUGCGGCACAGGACUGUGCCCUGUGCUGUCCCCUGCACCCCGGCUCAGCUGAGCUGGGGAACACUGCUGUCGUGUGAAGUCACAGUGGCCUUGUUGGUGCCCACAGGGCUGUGUGGAUGGAGGAAGCUGUCCCUGCCCAGUGCAUCCCCCAGGUCAUCACGGGGACGCAGGAGGCAGGCCCUGCCCUGCCCUCUCCUCACAGGUCUGUUGCAGGGACUCCAGAAACCAUUCUGGGAGCCGUGGAUGGGGGCGGAGCUGGGGUUUGGUGCAGUUUCCAGGGUGCAGUACAGCAGGGCCUGAAUACUGGCCCUGGACUCCCUUUUCCAGAACACCAGGUGUGGCCACCUGGGGCUCAGGUACACAGUGGGGUCUCUCGGAAGCCACCGUGUGGUUCUUUCACAGGCACGUUUAUUUUGCUGAAAUAAAAAGUUUUUAAUCGGG